AUUCCACAAGUGUCGCUUCGCUCUCUUCAGCGCACUUGGCGAGCUGGUGAGGUGAGAGGGAUACUGCGAGAGGGCUAGGGGCGGCCAGUCCGGGGCUGCCGGCCAAGGCUAGGCGCUGCCAGCCCGAUUCUCCUCUGCUCUCCACCCCCGCCUCACCCAGUGGCCGGCCGGACCUGCACCCCGCGCUUGACCCCGCUCAUCCUCCCCCCGCCCGGCCGGGCGCGCUCCUCCCCGGCCGGCCCCUCGGCGCGCGGCGCGCUGGAGGCGAACGCGGGCUGAGGCGAACGCGGGCUGAGCCGAGCGCAGUGGCCGCCGACCACCGAGCGCCCCGCGCCGCUCCCUGCAUGUGCGGCCCGCGGCGGCUCGCAGCUCCCGGCAGCAGCCUCGGCAGCUUCGGCCGCGCCUCGAGAGGCGGCCGCAGAGGCUCCAGCGGCGGCCGAGCGGCCGAGCCCGGGCUGGGAGACACCAUGCGCCGCGUCCUUCGGCUGCUCCUCGGUUGCUUCCUCACCGAGCUGUGCGCCCGCGUGUGCCGGGCGCAGGAGCGAGCGGGACACGGGCAGCUGGCGCAACUGGGCGGCGUGUUGCUGCUGGCGGGGGGCAACCGCUCCGGGGCCGCCUCCGGAGAGGCCAGCGAGGGCGCUGAGGCAUCGGACGCGCCCCCGACCCGGGCGCCCACGCCGGACUUCUGCCGGGGCUACUUCGAUGUCAUGGGCCAGUGGGACCCGCCGUUCAACUGCAGCUCGGGCGACUUCAUCUUCUGCUGCGGGACUUGUGGCUUCCGGUUCUGCUGCACGUUUAAGAAGCGGCGACUGAACCAAAGCACCUGCACCAACUACGACACGCCGCUCUGGCUCAACACCGGCAAGCCCCCCGCCCGCAAGGACGACCCCUUGCACGACCCCACCAAGGACAAGACCAACCUGAUCGUCUACAUCAUCUGCGGGGUGGUGGCCGUCAUGGUGCUCGUGGGCAUCUUCACCAAGCUGGGGCUGGAGAAAGCGCACCGGCCCCAAAGGGAGCACAUGUCCAGGGCCCUUGCGGAUGUCAUGAGACCACAGGGCCACUGCAACACUGAUCACAUGGAGAGAGACCUAAACAUCGUUGUCCACGUCCAGCAUUAUGAGAACAUGGACACGAGAACCCCCAUAAAUAAUCUUCAUGCCACCCAGAUGAACAACGCAGUGCCCACCUCUCCUCUGCUCCAGCAGAUGGGCCAUCCACAUUCGUACCCGAACCUGGGCCAGAUCUCCAACCCCUAUGAACAGCAGCCACCAGGAAAAGAGCUCAACAAGUACGCCUCCUUAAAGGCAGUCGGAAGUUCUGAUGGUGACUGGGCAGUAUCGACACUUAAGUCACCAAAAGCUGACAAGGUCAAUGACGACUUCUACACCAAGCGACGGCACCUGGCUGAGCUGGCUGCCAAGGGGAACUUACCUCUGCACCCCGUAAGAGUGGAGGACGAGCCCCGGGCCUUCAGCCCUGAGCACGGUCCUGCCAAGCAGAAUGGACAGAAGUCCCGCACCAACAAGAUGCCCCCACAUCCCCUGGCCUACACCUCUACCACCAACUUUAAGGGCUGGGACCCCAACGAGCAGUCCCUCCGGCGGCAGGCUUACAGCAACAAGGGCAAGCUUGGCACGGCCGAGACAGGCUCCAGCGACCCCUUGGGAACUCGCCCCCAGCACUACCCACCCCCACAGCCAUACUUCAUCACCAACAGCAAAACAGAAGUGACUGUCUGAGCUUUCACCACAGGGAGCACCCUGGAGACCACACUCAACUGAGAGAGGCAAAAAACAACCCCGCCCACACCCUCCCCAUCCUCCCCUAAUACAUGCGUCCACACACUCACUCUCAACAAGAACCAACUCUAAACCUACUGGGGACACAGAGUCGCGCUUUUCCUAGGUCAUGCCUGUAACGUGUCGGCGGGCAGCUGAGAAAGACCGAAGCGUGGACAUUCAGCAAUACAGCAAAGGGGAAAAUGAGGCACACUCUUUCCACUUCAGGCCCAAGAUGGCCAACUCACAUGCCCAAACCGUGGGGCUGAGUUUUCUUUUCCUCCUAACUUGAAACUGAAAUCCAUGGUGACAAAAUAUAAAAGUAGCACAAUUUAGAGAAAUUGUCCAUUUGAGCACAUACACUACUUGCCACGUGCUGUCUGUUUCUAGGUUCGAAAGCCAGGGUGGAAAUGGGGGUAGAGAAUGAGGGAGGACACAAGAGAAGAGUGUAUUCUGGAAGAGGAGUUGUUCUGGGAGGAAUUUGCCCACAUUAGAAGCAUUUUUCUAAUUCCAAGAAGUGGUGACGUGGACGUAAAAUUUUGACGAGCAUGAAACAGUAACUGGACCCCAACCAUUCUAUUUAUAGUACUUUUCAUAUCAUCCAUGUUGAAAGCAAAAAACAACACACCCUCAAACUCACAGAAAGUAAAUAGACCCUGAACCCACCGACAAUGAUGGGAAGGAAAAAACAAAAAACAAAAAACAUUUUAGAGAACUCCCAUAAGGACCAUGACCGUGGAAAUGGGAGGGAUGGGCUUUUACGGAGAGGGUCCGGAGAGUAUCAAAUAACUUUUUAAAAAGAGGAUUAAAAUGUAAGCCCACUACAAAACAGAUAAAAACGGCAAAUUAGGUGUUUUUUUUUUUUCAAAAAUCUUGAAGACUUGUUGACAUUAACAACAACAAAUCCACAGUUGGAAAAGUCCACAGGAGAUCAGAUGAGGAUCCAGAAGCCUCUGAUUUCUGGGUUUUGCCUCCAAGACCUGAAACAGCCACAGAAACAAGUCCUCUAUAAACUGUAUGUCCCUGACAUCCCUUUCCCUUCAGCGCGUUGCCGCCGCCGCUGCCAAACUUCAACUGCUUUGGACUGAAAAUGUCAUAAGCGUGGGUGGUGCCUUCAAUGUGUUACUGUUGUUUAAUGACAGUCUUGUUUCCCAAGUGCAACCUGUGUUCUUUUAGCCUUCCUUCCUCUUCUUUUUCUGCAGUAGUAGAAGAUGUUUCCAUCCUUCCUUUGUAGGUGAGCCCACCCCAUAACACCCUCUGAGGGGCUGCUACAAUGUCAGGGGUACCCAAGAACGAAGACCUCCCUACUCUCUACACUAUCAAAAUUAGUCCUUCCAUUUUCUAGCCCUCUCAAACCUGUCAGAUGUUUCUUGGUCCCGUAAUUCCCAUGGUCCCUCCAAAUUACCUCCCCACAUACUUCAUGUGUUCAUCUCCCAUCCAGAAUGUCCUGAGGUUGUUUUUCUGGUUGGUUCUCAUAAUCCAUAGUCCUUGGGGUCCCAGCAAAGUCAGUUUUCCUACAAGUUGUGUUUGUUUUGUGGAAGCCCAAAGAAGUGGAUUGAGAGAGAAGAGAUUUUUAUCUAAGGUGGAAGGUUUUUCAACUAGCCCCUAAAGGUCUUUGGUAGUUAAUUAACAUUCAACAGACCCACAGCAACUCUGGUGUCAGAAGCUAUAAAUGGUCUGGCCAAACAAGACUCAGAGUAUUUUCUGAAAUCCUGAGCUGCAAGGUUCUGCCUCACCUGUCUCUCCACUCUGACAUCACGAAAUCAGCAAAACCAGAUAUUUAUUCUCCUCACUCCCAGCAGAUACGAGGACACCAACAAUGCAGUUGAUCCCUCUGGGCCUGAGUCUCCCAUCUGAAACAUGGGGAAUUGGGGUAGGUCAAGCUUUUUGAAACUGCAAAACCUCUACCUGUUUUUAAAAAUGAGAUCUUUUGACCAGGCACAGUGGCUCACACCUAAAAUCCCAGCACUUUGGGAGGCUGAAGCAGGUGGAUCAUCUGAGGUCAGGAGUUUGAGAUCAGCCUGGUCAACAUGGUGAAACCCCGUCUCUACUAAAAAUACAAACAUUAGCUGGGCAUGGUGGUGGGUGCCUGUAAUCCCAACUACUCGAGAGGCUGAGGCAGGAGAAUCGCUUAAACUUGGGAGGUUGCAGUGAGCUGAGACCACACCACUGCCCUCUAGCCUGGGUGACGGAGUGAGACUAUCUCAAAAAAAAAAAAAAAAAGAAAAAAAAAGAGAUCUUUCAAAGAACGCAUAAUAGGAGAUCUCCAUGUAUAAAAAGGUACCAUGCUGUACAAAGCUGGGGUCAGAGAUUUAGUGCCCACCUUCUCAGCCUCCUUGGGAAGACCCCAGAGCUUCCCAGAGUCAAGUAAAUACCACUGGGCAUGGUCAGAGUUUCCUUGACGUUAAUGAGCUAUGUACCUGCAACACACUUUGGCAUCUCUGUAUAUCACCUUCACAAUAUUUGUAUCUAAAUUGAUUCAUUUUAAUGCAUUUUGUUUUUAAAAUGAAAACUUCCUGUCUUCAUCACAAAUUUAAAAAAAAUCAUCAGUUGCCAUAAAUAGAAAGCAAACAUAAAAAUAAGUACAAAGGAAACAAGCAGCGAUGAUUAAAUUCCAGCUGGAGUCUGUUGUCUGUGAGUCUGAACUAAAGCCUGGGGUUCUUUCUUUCUCUCUCCAUCUCUCUGUUUCUGUUUCUCUCUCUCUCUUAAAAUGAUAUCAUCAGGUAUUAAAUAAUUGUUAAAAAUACCAGCACCCAAUGAAGACUUUCUCUUUGUACUAAUAAGAUGGACCAAAAAGUAAAUGAAAGGGGAAUCAUUUCCUAUGCAAGUCAGUGUUGAACAAUGCUGUAGCUAUGUACUGCCUAUGAUCAUUGUGCAUACACUAGGGGUGCAUAGCCCACACUUCAGAAAACCCUGGGUUGACUUAUCUGUGAGGCUCUUUCCAGCUCAAAGUUUCCAUAAUUCUUAUCUCCCUUUUACCUCGUGGUUGCUCUUUGCCCCCAGUCCACUUCGUCCCACCCUUAUCUCAACUCUGAUUAAGAGUCUUUCUUGGCCUCUAAAUCUGUAGUAUUGUAUUCCUUCUGCAUGCUCCUUCUCCUCUGAAUAAACUUCAUCAAUUGAACUGGGCUCCUUGGGGUCUGCAGUUGUAAUUUUGGCAGCAAAGGUGCAGACUGGUCAUUAAGAUGUAGCCACAAUGAUGGCCCAAGAAGGACACGUACUUUCCAAGUAGUCCUGUCUAGGAUGGAAAGCUCAGGAAGUGCUUCAUAGUUUAUUAUCUUCCAGUUGGUUUUGGGAGAUGAACUGAAGAGGGAAGUUUGGAUAGGGAAGGUCUUUUUAUUCUUUUUUUUUUAAUGUAUCCAUGGAGUAUUUAUUAUUAUUAUUAUUAUUAUUAUUAUUAUUAUUAUACUUUAAGUUUUAGGGUACAUGUGCACAAUGUGCAGGUUAGUUACAUAUGUAUACACGUGUCAUGCUGGUGUGCUGCACCCAUUAACUCGUCAUUUAGCAUUAGCUAUAUCUCCUAAUGCUAUCCCUCCCCCCUCCCCCCACCCCACAACAGUCCCCAGAGUGUGAUGUUCCCCUUCUUGUGUCCAUGUGUUCUCAUUGUUCAAUUCCCAUCUAUGAGUGAGAACAUGCAGUGUUUGGUUUUUUUGUCCUUGCGAUAGUUUACUGAGAAUGAUGAUUUCCAAUUUCAUCCAUGUCCCUACAAAGGACAUGAACUCAUCAUUUUUUAUGGCUGCAUAGUAUUCCAUGGUGUAUAUGUGCCACAUUUUCUUAAUCCAGUCUAUCCUUGUUGGACUUUUGGGUUGGUUCCAAGUCUUUGCUAUUGUGAAUAGUGCCGCAAUAAACAUACGUGUGCAUGUGUCUUUAUAGCAGCAUGAUUUAUAGUCCUUUGGGUAUAUACCCAGUAAUGGGAUGGCUGGGUCAAAUGGUAUUUCUAGUUCUAGAUCCCUGAGGAAUCGCCACACUGACUUCCACAAUGGUUGAACUAGUUUACAGUCCCACCAGCAGUGUAAAAGUGUUCCUAUUUCUCCACAUCCUCUCCAGCACCUGUUGUUUCCUGACUUUUUAAUGAUUGCCAUUCUAACUGGCGUGAGAUGGUAUCUCAUUGUGGUUUUGAUUUGCAUUUCUCUGAUGGCCAGUGAUGAUGAGCAUUUUUUCAUGUGUCUUUUGACUGCAUAAAUGUCUUUUGAGAAGUGUCUGUUCAUAUCCUUCGCCCACUUUUUGAUGGGGUUGUUUGUUUUUUUCUUGUAAAUUUGUUUGAGUUCAUUGUAGAUUCUGGAUAUUAGCCCUUUGUCAGAUGAGUAGGUUGCGAAAAUUUUCUCCCAUUUUGUAGGUUGCCUGUUCACUCUGAUGGUAGUUUCUUUUGCUGUGCAGAAGCUCUUUAGUUUAAUUAGAUCCCAUUUGUCAAUUUUGGCUUCCUCUUGGGAGGGUAGACAGACCUCACAAUAUGGAAAGACGGGACAACCUAUGGAACUAUCUGUGACUUCCAUGUACCAAGACAAGGACGCUAUAGCUAGGGUAGUGAGACCUAGAAGAGAGAAACCAGAACAAAGCAGACAGGCUGUCCUCUUCCUAAUUCCAUGCCCUGACAUCAGCCCCUAUUUUUUGCCUUUAGCUGUCCCCCAGUUUCCAACCCAAUGGGACCAGAGUCUGACUUCCCUUUGCCCUUUCACAGUGUCUCAGCCUCCAUCUGCCUUGGGCUCCGCCUGGCCUCCCCAUCUAACUCUUCCCAGUUUUUUGUGUAAAUGGAGCAUAUUUUAUGUGCGAAUAUUUUAGUAACCGUAUGUUCUGCAAGUAAACCUGUGUUAAUACUUGUCAACAACUGCAGAGUUUAUGAUACGAAUAAUUCUUCCUACAAUGAAGAAAAAAACACAUUUGUUUGUUUUCUAAGAAUGUUUAUUUGUAAACAUAUGUAUUCACUAUAUUAAUAUGAAUUUCUUACCUGGCAAUAAAACUGAUUAUAUGUGA